AGCAAGUGUCCGCUGUACCUGGCCUGCUACCACCUAAAGACUGAGCGCAGCCAGCAGGACUGGGAAAGGCAGGGCGAUGAUGGCAGUGAAGGAUGGAGUCUCACUCUGUCGCCUAGGCUGGAGUGCCGUGGUGCGAUCUCGCUCACUGCAACCUCCACCUCCCAGGUUCAAGCAAUUCUCUGCCUCAGCAUCCCGAGUAGCUGGGAUUAUAGGUGCCCGCCACCAUGCCCAGCUCAUUUUUGUAUUUUUAGUAGAGGCGGGGUUUCACCAUCUUGGCCAGGCUGGUCUUGAAUUCCUGACCUCAAGUGAUCCACCCGCCUUGGCCUCCCAAAGUGUUGGGAUUACAGGAGUGAGCCACCUCGCCCAGCCAACUUGACAUAACUUUUAAAGAUGGAUUGCCAAGCUGAGGUGAACUGCGGGCUUCAUCUGGUUAUUCAAACAUCAUCGCUUCCUGAAAAAAACAAAGUUGAAUUCAAGCUAAAUAAAGACACAUCGUCAUUCCCCGGUAGACUUUUACAACAUGACCUUGAAAGAAACUACUCAAGUAGGCAAGGUGAUCAUAUUAAUUUGGUGAGCUCAUCAUUGUCAUCAUUUCCUAUUCUUCAACGUUCUUCUGAAGAGAAAAUUCUUUACUCAGACAGGUUGAGCCUAGAAAGACAAAAGCUGACCGUAUGUCCUAUCAUCAAUGGGGAAGACCACCUUCGUUUGUUGAACUUUCAACACAAUUUUAUAACUCGGAUACAAAAUAUUUCUAAUCUACAGAAGUUAAUAUCGUUGGAUUUAUAUGAUAACCAGAUUGAAGAAAUUAGUGGGCUUUCGACUCUGAGAUGUCUUCGUGUCCUUCUGUUGGGGAAAAACAGAAUCAAGAAAAUCUCAAAUCUGGAGAAUCUAAAAAGCUUAGAUGUCUUGGAUCUUCAUGGAAAUCAGAUUACCAAAAUUGAAAAUAUUAAUCAUUUGUGUGAGUUGAGAGUUUUAAAUCUUGCCAGGAACUUUUUAAGUCAUGUUGAUAAUCUUAAUGGGCUGGAUUCACUAACUGAACUUAACUUGCGACACAAUCAAAUCACUUUCGUGAGAGAUGUGGAUAAUUUGCCCUGCCUCCAACAUCUCUUUCUCAGCUUUAACAAUAUAUCUAGUUUUGACAGUGUUUCCUGCCUUGCUGACUCUUCUUCCCUCUCGGACAUCACCUUUGAUGGCAAUCCCAUAGCUCAAGAGUCAUGGUACAAACACACUGUCCUUCAGAAUAUGAUGCAGCUGCGCCAGCUAGAUAUGAAGAGAAUCACGGAAGAAGAAAGGCGUAUGGCAUCUGUUUUAGCCAAAAAAGAGGAAGAGAAGAAGCGGGAAAGUCAUAAACAAUCUUUGCUUAAGGAGAAGAAAAGGUUAACAAUUAACAACGUAGCUCGACAGUGGGACUUGCAACAACAACGAGUAGCCAAUAUUGCUACAAAUGAAGAUAGAAAAGAUUCUGACUCUCCUCAGGACCCCUGUCAGAUUGAUGGAAGCACCCUCUCUGCAUUCCCAGAGGAAACAGGGCCUCUAGACUCAGGACUCAACAAUGCUUUACAAGGUUUAUCUGUCAUAGACACAUACCUUGUUGAAGUGGACGGGGAUACACUUUCCCUAUAUGGCUCAGGAGCACUGGAAUCUCUGGAUAGGAAUUGGAGUGUUCAAACAGCAGGAAUGAUCACAACAGUCUCCUUCACUUUCAUAGAAUUUGAUGAAAUCGUCCAAGUGCUUCCUAAACUGAAGAUUAAGUUUCCUAAUUCUCUGCACCUUAAAUUCAAGGAAACAAAUCUUGUAAUGCUGCAGCAAUUUAACGCACUAGCCCAACUCCGUCGUAUUGACCAGUUGACAAUUGAUCCUCAAGGAAAUCCAGUUGUCAAUUUUACACUCUGGAAAUACUAUGUACUGUUUAGGCUAAGCCAUUUCAGUAUGCAGAAAAUAAAUGGAACAGAGGUGACACAGAAUGAUAUGAUAAUGGCUGAAAGGCUCUUUGGAAUCCUAGCACAUGUAGCAUCUUCUGAGUUACCCCAGUAUCGUCUGAUUUCCAUUCUGGGUGAUGCCAGGAAAAAGCAAUUUCGGUAUCUACUAGAAUCCAAAGGAAAAAAACCUGGUAUUAUCAACGAAGAAAAUAAUGACAGCAAAAGACUUGUAGGAGAAAACACAAAUCGUGCUACAUUAAAUUAUACUACAAGAGACUUUUAUAAUGAAAAGCUAGAGGAAAUAAAGGAAAAGAAGAAAUUCUGUAAAACAUAUAUAGAAGACCUUGUGAAGGAAGCCACAGAAAUCAACAUGAAAAAUGAGGCUUUGCAGAAGCUUUGGCCACAGAUGUUCAUUGAGCUUGUUAGGGAUGCAGUCAUAGAAAUUCGCAAUAAAAAUUCCUAUAUGAAGCUCUGCCUACAGCAGAUAACAGACCAAAAAUAAAAAUGGCCUUUAGUUACAGUUGAUUUUGGCAGUUUUAUUUUUUGAAGGUUGAAAAUAUGCAGGUUAUACAUGUUAAAACAACAACAACACUAUCCUAUAAACUAGAAAGACUAGUAUAAAAGCAUUAUUGCCCACUGUUCUCAUAGCUAAAAGUUAAGAAGGAAGGAAGGAAAGCAGGAGAAAGGAAGGAUUAAUUGCCUGUAUGUGAGGACCAAACAACCUUUGGGAACUAAACAGUUUUCAGAGAUGGCGUGGCACUGCAUCCUUGGUUCUUGCUUUGAUUGGUGCCCUGCUAUAGCCCAAAGCACGUAGUAUUUGCUGAUGAUUCAGCAUGAGCUGCAUCUACCUACUUUUAGCUGAUAAUUUUCAGUUAUUUCCCUUUUUAUUUUAUGUCAUGAUUUCAAAGCCAAAAAUAUGUUCUUUUUAUGAGUGAAGAAUAAACUUACUAACAAAUUAGUCAAAAUAAAGUAUGUUUGCCUCCUUAAUUCAGUCAGAAUUGUCAUAUUUAUUGUAUGUUCCUCUUUAGUUAGGUACGGUUCCUGCUAUUCACCUAUAUGGAGGAUGCCCCAUUCUUCUAGGAAUGCAUUCUCAGGGAACCACAGGAGGUCCUGGGAAUCACUAUGGGCAGAGAAUAUGCAAAUGAGUCAAAACUGGGAUAGGAAGAAAAUGUUUUGUCUUAGGAGAUCCUGAAUGACUAUAAAAUGCUGUUACAAAGCAGUAAAUCUGCUUCUCUGAAAGAUGUUUCCUUCCAUUGUUAGCUCUCAAAUGCUCUUUUAAUAGACAUGCAUGUGUACCUGUGUCUCAGAAGUAUUAGGGAUGCAUGAGUGAAGGGUUCUAAUUUUUAAAAUUUCAUUUGAAGAUCAAAUUCAUGCUGGUGAGAAGGGUAGUAGGAGCCUAUUACCAUAGCUAGAGAUGAUGCCACUUCAGAAAAACAAUCUUAGUCAAUAAAUAGGAAUUUUUCGGUUUGCUUAGAUUUUACCUAGCAGCUAUUAUGUCAGCAGGACCACCAGGAUAUGGGAAAACAGGACUAGAAGAUGUACGACAGCAAAGACAUGCAGAGACAUGCAGAGACACCUGGAAGGAAGCUAGGUAAGCUGCUAUUGCGGUUCUGAGAAAGACCCACAUCCUUAAGAUCUCUUGAUUACUCUUCUCCCAAAAGGCGUGCUUAACUUUAACAGGUUACCAUUUUUCUGAUCAUAGCCUUAAAAGGCUGUCCUGGUUUUUUCUUUUUCUUUUUUUUUUUUUGAGACAGAGUCUUGCUCUGUCACCCAGGCUGGAGUGCAGUGGCGCGAUCUCGGCUCACUGCAAGCUCCGCUUCCCAGGUUCACGCCAUUCUCCUGCCUCAGCCUCCCAAGUAGCUGGGUCUACAGGUGCCCGCCACCAUGCCCAGCUAAGUUUUUGUAUUUUUAGUAGAGACGGGGUUUCACCAUGUUAGCCAGGAUGGUCUCGAUCUCCUGACCUCAUGAUCCGCCUGCCUCGGCCUCCCAAAGUGCUGGGAUUACAGGUGUGAGCCACCAUGCCUGUCCUGUCCUGGUUUUUUCAUCUUGGCACUUAGGCCAUCAGCUUACUAGUGUGUAACCUCAGUUUCCUCCUGAUAGCACACACUUCGUAAGAUAGUCAUGAGAAUCAAAAGAAACAAUGCAUGUAAAGCAUUUCUCAUCAUGCCUGGCACACAGCAAACACCCAAUACGUUGAGCUUUAAUUAUUACUCUUUUGGCUGUAGGUUGAACAAUAGGGUUGGUGCCCUAGGACAGAGGAGCUAUUAGCAUUGCUUUCUGAUCCUUUAGCCUCUCCAAACUGAAACAUAUGGACCAUUUCUCAUCUGGCUAGUAAACACUUAUCUCUCCUGGGCUUAUAUCUUGUUUGGUAUAGAAAUGAGAUCCCAGCUUGAAGGUGAUGUUGAGAGGAGAACCAAGAGUAUAUUGUCUGUGGGAUUCUGGCAGAUUGGAAAGAUGUAAGAACUUGUGACUCUUUGGGAGUCUGGGUAACUGUUCCCACUCUAGGCUUUGCAGAUGAAUGGACCUAGCUGUUUAGUAAUCUGUCCAGCUUCCUGCAUGUCUGUUCUCCCCUAACCCUCCCAUCCCUGCUGCUAAAGAGACUUGACACUCACAUGCUUUCUUGGCCCAGUCACCCUGGGAAUCUUAGGAACACUAAGUCAGCACUCAAUGAAAUGGCAGCAAGCCAUCCCAGCCACUGCUGGCUCUAUGCAGACCUGCUUCAGGCCUGGUAAUAGGGUCUCUCUCUUGUUCCUGAAACCAAGCCUCUUUAUUCCUCAGCUUUGGUCUCUGCUUCCUUCCUACCUGAGUUCCCUUUCGCUCCUACCUGCUCCCACUACCCCAUACUGAUUUCUACUUCUUGAAUCCUUACUUUGUCGGGUCUCAAACGUCGAAUGGCGAUCCUCCCAUCUAGUUCUACACUCCAAACUCAUUUUGCGUUCUGAAGUUCCUUGGUGAAGAUAAUCCCCAGAUAAAAAGACAAGGAGACCUGGGUCUGCUGGGUUAGGGAUCAAGUGAGGGUCCUAUGUUGUAAGUGAGUGGUGAUCUAGGGAACAAAUUGCCAUUUCUUCUUGGAAUUUUCCAGGGUUUUCAGGGAAGGGGAAGAGAUGCAAAUCCCAUAGUCUGAGACUCUCUAGGCUAGUGUGUGCUGAAGAAUUGCUUUUUUUCAAAAGGGAUCUCACGCAGAAACACUAUUGCAUUUGCCUCAAAAGCAGAAACAUUUAGUACCCCCAUUUAGGGAGAUACUGUACCCGAUGUUCUGGUACAGCAGCUGGAUGGUGAAGUGUGCUGCUACACCUGAGGAUGGUUACCAAGUGUGCAGGUGGACCUGAGGCUUGUUAACUGUGCUGCUGAGUCAGAGGAUGGUGCUGGUAUCAGCUCCUCACUUCCUGAGCUUCAUUCCACUGAAGGCCUGGCAUGUAAGACAGUGCAACCCUACCAUGCUCCUGAUCUAUUCCUGAUUGGGCAAGGAAUGCACUGGGAUUCAUAUUCUCUUCAAUGAGUAAUCAUCAUAACAACAAAGAUUCAUUGAGCAAUGUCUUGCACUAUUAUAAGCUCUUUGUAUACAUUCUCAUUUAAUCUCCUAACACUGCGAUAUAUAUAUGAUAGCAAUCCCAUUUGAACACUAGAAAACUGAGGCAUAGAGAGGAUGAAAAAAAACGUAACUAAGGGUAUUUCAACCAAUAAAUAGUAGACAGUACCCACAUUCACUGUUAGUCUUAAGGAUCUGGCAUCUGGGAAGAAUUUUGAUGUCCAUGGUCGUUCCUAAUCCACUUUCAUGUUUUGUCAUUAUGCUGAGGAAUAGCAAAUAAAAGAUGAGAAUUUCUCAACUGUGUCUACAUGUGAAGCAUAUCGUAGACAUUAUGUGCGGUAUAAAUACUAACAAAUGUAUAAGUACACAUGUACAAUAUUGUGUAUUAUUUAAGGAUAUACAUAUUAAAGUGUAAAAUAUUGGCAGCUGGAUUCAUUGCAAUAAUGUGUAGAGAAUCAACUUCAGGAGGGGGCAAUAAUUAAAUUAGGGGGACCAGUUGGGAAGGUACUGCAUUAUUCUAGGCAAGAGAUAAUUGUGACUUGGAUCAAGGUGAUAGCGGCAGAGGCGUCAGAAAGUAGUUGGAUCUUGGGUAUAUUUUAAAGAUGAAGCAACAAGAUUUACUGACAGAACUGGAUAUGGAGUAUGAGAAACAGUAGUCAAUGAUGGCCACAAGGUUUUUGGCUUGAACUACCGAAAAGAUUGAGUUGCCAUCAACUGAGAUGAGAGCAAUCUGUGAAUGGAACAUCUGCUGGGAGGAAGGAUCAGGAAUUCCGUCUUAUGGAAUACACAAUGCAUCUCAACAUGUACAAUAUAUACAAGAUAUACCACACAUCUCAGCAUAUGUUGAGAUGGUUGUUAAAUAUCCAAGUGCAGGUGUUAAGUAGGUGUGAAUAUGAGUUGGGAGUUGAGAAGUAUAGAUUGGGCUAGAAUUAUAGAAUUUGGAGUCAUUGGCGUAUAGCAGUACUUGUUUAUGCUAUCUUUAUAUUUAAGAGAAUAAACCUAUCACUUGCUAAAUAAGA